AGAGCAAACACCCAGCCCAGGGCCCCUGGAUUUGAGCAGUGCCUCGGAGCAGAGGGAUAUCUGCCGCAUCAGGUGCCACCCCGGGUGAAGGAUGCCACUCUGGGUGUUCUUCUUUGUGAUCCUCACCCUCAGCAACAGCUCCCACUGCUCCCCACCUCCCCCUUUGACCCUCAGGAUGCGGCGGUAUGCAGAUGCCAUCUUCACCAACAGCUACCGGAAGGUGCUGGGCCAGCUGUCCGCCCGCAAGCUGCUCCAGGACAUCAUGAGCAGGCAGCAGGGAGAGAGCAACCAAGAGCGAGGAGCAAGGGCACGGCUUGGUCGUCAGGUAGACAGCAUGUGGGCAGAACAAAAGCAAAUGGAAUUGGAGAGCAUCCUGGUGGCCCUGCUGCAGAAGCACAGCAGGAACUCCCAGGGAUGAAGAUUCCUCCUGUGACCCGGGCUACCUGUAGCCAAAAUGCAACUGGAUCCAGUUAAUCCUCUCAUUUCUGACCCACUUUUUCCUUUGAAAAUACAAUAAAAUUCCCCCAUACCGGUGUGCAUUUAAA